ACACUCUACCACCAUGAAUCUACUUCUGAUCCUUACCUUUGUUGCAGCUGCUGUUGCUGCCCCCUUUGAUGAUGAUGACAAGAUCGUUGGGGGCUACAUCUGUGAGGAGAAUUCUGUCCCCUACCAGGUGUCCUUGAAUUCUGGCUACCACUUCUGCGGUGGCUCCCUCAUCAGCGAACAGUGGGUGGUGUCAGCAGGUCACUGCUACAAGUCGGCAAUUAACUCAAAAUUAUCAGGAAGAGGGUGUGAAUAUCACCGCAUCCAGGUGAGACUGGGAGAGCACAACAUCGAAGUCCUGGAGGGGAAUGAACAGUUCAUCAAUGCGGCCAAGAUCAUCCGCCACCCCAAAUACAACAGCCGGACUCUGGACAAUGACAUCCUGCUGAUCAAGCUCUCCUCACCUGCCGUCAUCAAUUCCCGCGUGUCCGCCAUCUCUCUGCCCACUGCCCCUCCAGCUGCUGGCACCGAGUCCCUCAUCUCCGGCUGGGGCAACACUCUGAGUUCUGGUGCCGACUACCCAGACGAGCUGCAGUGCCUGGAUGCUCCUGUGCUGAGCCAGGCUGAGUGUGAAGCCUCCUACCCUGGAAAGAUUACCAACAACAUGUUCUGUGUGGGCUUCCUCGAGGGAGGCAAGGAUUCCUGCCAGGGUGAUUCUGGUGGCCCUGUGGUCUCCAAUGGAGAGCUCCAAGGAAUUGUCUCCUGGGGCUAUGGCUGUGCCCAGAAGAACAGGCCUGGAGUCUACACCAAGGUCUACAACUAUGUGGACUGGAUUAAGGACACCAUAGCUGCCAACAGCUAAAGCCCCUGGUCCCUCUGCAGUCUCUAUACCAAUAAAGUGACCCUGCUCUCAC